AGCUGAACUCGGCGCCUGGAAAGAUGGAGGCAGCGGAGACAGAGGCGGAAGCUGCAGCCCUAGAGGUCCUGGCUGAGGUGGCAGGCAUCUUGGAACCUGUAGGCCUGCAGGAGGAGGCAGAACUGCCAGCCAAGAUCCUGGUUGAGUUUGUGGUGGACUCUCAGAAGAAAGACAAGCUGCUCUGCAGCCAGCUUCAGGUAGCGGAUUUCCUGCAGAACAUCCUGGCUCAGGAGGACACUGCUAAGGGUCUCGACCCCUUGGCUUCUGAAGACACGAGCCGACAGAAGGCAAUUGCAGCUAAGGAACAAUGGAAAGAGCUGAAGGCCACCUACAGGGAGCACGUAGAGGCCAUCAAAAUUGGCCUCACCAAGGCCCUGACUCAGAUGGAGGAAGCCCAGAGGAAACGGACACAACUCCGGGAAGCCUUUGAGCAGCUCCAGGCCAAGAAACAAAUGGCCAUGGAGAAACGCAGAGCAGUCCAGAACCAGUGGCAGCUACAACAGGAGAAGCAUCUGCAGCAUCUGGCGGAGGUUUCUGCAGAGGUGAGGGAGCGUAAGACAGGGACUCAGCAGGAGCUUGACAGGGUGUUUCAGAAACUUGGAAACCUGAAGCAGCAGGCAGAACAGGAGCGGGACAAGCUGCAGAGGUAUCAGACCUUCCUCCAGCUUCUGUAUACCCUGCAGGGUAAGCUGUUGUUCCCUGAGGCUGAGGCUGAGGCAGAGAAUCUUCCAGAUGAUAAACCCCAGCAGCCGACUCGACCCCAGGAGCAGAGUACAGGAGACACCAUGGGGAGAGACCCUGGUGUGUCCUUCAAGGCUGUUGGUCUACAACCUGCUGGAGAUGUAAAUUUGCCAUGACUUCCUGGAGGACAGCAGCAUGGAGAAAGAUCCUAGAAAAGGCCUCUGACUUCCCUCACCUCCCAACCAUCAUUACAGGAAAGACUGUGAACUCCUGAGUUCAGCUUGAUUUCUGACUACAUCCCAGCAAGCUCUGGCAUCUGUGGAUUAAAAUCCCUGGAUCUCUCUCAGUUGUGUAUUUGUUCAUCUUCAUAUGCUGGCAGGAACAACUAUUAAUACAGAUACUCAGAAGCCAAUAACAUGACAGGAGCUGGGACUGGUUUGAACACAGGGUGUGCAGAUGGGGAGGGGGUACUGGCCUUGGGCCUCCUAUGAUGCAGACAUGGUGAAUUUAAUUCAAGGAGGAGGAGAAUGUUUUAGGCAGGUGGUUAUAUGUGGGAAGAUAAUUUUAUUCAUGGAUCCAAAUGUUUGUUGAGUCCUUUCUUUGUGCUAAGGUUCUUGCGGUGAACCAGAAUUAUAACAGUGAGCUCAUCUGACUGUUUUAGGAUGUACAGCCUAGUGUUAACAUUCUUGGUAUCUUUUUGUGCCUUAUCUAAAACAUUUCUCGAUCACUGGUUUCAGAUGUUCAUUUAUUAUAUUCUUUUCAAAGAUUCAGAGAUUGGCUUUUGUCAUCCACUAUUGUAUGUUUUGUUUCAUUGACCUCUAGUGAUACCUUGAUCUUUCCCACUUUCUGUUUUCGGAUUGGAGAAGAUGUACCUUUUUUGUCAACUCUUACUUUUAUCAGAUGAUCAACUCACGUAUUUGGAUCUUUAUUUGUUUUCUCAAAUAAAUAUUUAAGGUUAUACAUUUCUUCUGACUUCCUUUAUUUUCACAAUCAUUCAAUUCAUAGCAUUUCCUAUAUUCUGUUAUAAUUAUUUCAUUGAUUCAUAAAUUUCUUUGAAAAAUAAUUUGGUCUUCUAUUGAUUGUGAGAAGAUAAUCUAAGUUUAAUUUGGUCAGAGAAUAUCAUCUGUUUAAUAAACUUUGAAAUUUGGUGAGUGAAUUAUCUUUUUUACUGAUAAA